GCCCCCGCCCCGCCCGGUCCAGCCAGCUCGGCCCGGGGGCUUCGGGCUGUCGGGCCGGCGCUCCCUUCUCUGCCAGGUGGCGAGUACACCUGCUCACGUAGGCGUCAUGAGGUCUCCGGUUCGAGACCUGGCCCGGAACGAUGGCGAGGAGAGCACGGACCGCACGCCUCUUCUACCGGGCGCCCCACGGGCCGAAGCCGCUCCAGUGUGCUGCUCUGCUCGUUACAACUUAGCAAUUUUGGCCUUUUUUGGUUUCUUCAUUGUGUAUGCAUUACGUGUGAAUCUGAGUGUUGCGUUAGUGGAUAUGGUAGAUUCAAAUACAACUUUAGAAGAUAAUAGAACUUCCAAGGCGUGUCCAGAGCAUUCUGCUCCCAUAAAAGUUCAUCAUAAUCAAACGGGUAAGAAGUACCAAUGGGAUGCAGAAACUCAAGGAUGGAUUCUCGGUUCCUUUUUUUAUGGCUACAUCAUCACACAGAUUCCUGGAGGAUAUGUUGCCAGCAAAAUAGGGGGGAAAAUGCUGCUAGGAUUUGGGAUCCUUGGCACUGCUGUCCUCACCCUGUUCACUCCCAUUGCUGCAGAUUUAGGAGUUGGACCACUCAUUGUACUCAGAGCACUAGAAGGACUAGGAGAGGGUGUUACAUUUCCAGCCAUGCAUGCCAUGUGGUCUUCUUGGGCUCCCCCUCUUGAAAGAAGCAAACUUCUUAGCAUUUCAUAUGCAGGAGCACAGCUUGGGACAGUAAUUUCUCUUCCUCUUUCUGGAAUAAUUUGCUACUAUAUGAAUUGGACUUAUGUCUUCUACUUUUUUGGUACUAUUGGAAUAUUUUGGUUUCUUUUGUGGAUCUGGUUAGUUAGUGACACACCACAAAAACACAAGAGAAUUUCCCAUUAUGAAAAGGAAUACAUUCUUUCAUCAUUAAGAAAUCAGCUUUCUUCACAGAAGUCAGUGCCGUGGGUACCCAUUUUAAAAUCCCUGCCACUUUGGGCUAUCGUAGUUGCACACUUUUCUUACAACUGGACUUUUUAUACUUUAUUGACAUUAUUGCCUACUUAUAUGAAGGAGAUCCUAAGGUUCAAUGUUCAAGAGAAUGGGUUUUUAUCUUCAUUGCCUUAUUUAGGCUCUUGGUUAUGUAUGAUCCUGUCUGGUCAAGCUGCUGACAAUUUAAGGGCAAAAUGGAAUUUUUCAACUUUAUGUGUUCGCAGAAUUUUUAGCCUUAUAGGAAUGAUUGGACCUGCAGUAUUCCUGGUAGCUGCUGGCUUCAUUGGCUGUGAUUAUUCUUUGGCCGUUGCUUUCCUAACUAUAUCAACAACACUGGGAGGCUUUUGCUCUUCUGGAUUUAGCAUCAACCAUCUGGAUAUUGCUCCUUCGUAUGCUGGUAUCCUCCUGGGCAUCACAAAUACAUUUGCCACUAUUCCAGGAAUGGUUGGGCCCGUCAUUGCUAAAAGUCUGACCCCUGAUGCUGGAGUACAAUGGCGCAAUCUCAGCUCACCACAACCUUUGCCUCCCGGGUUCCGGCGAUUUUCCUGCCUCAGCCUCCCGAAUAGCUGGGAUUACAGAACACUGUUGGAGAAUGGCAAACCGUGUUCUAUAUUGCUGCUGCUAUUAAUGUUUUUGGUGCCAUUUUCUUUACACUAUUCGCCAAAGGUGAAGUACAAAACUGGGCUCUCAAUGAUCACCAUGGACACAGACACUGAAGGAACCAAUAAAUAAUCCUGCCUCUAUUAAUGUAUUUUUAUUUAUCAUGUAACCUCAAAGUGCCUUCUGUAUUGUGUAAGCAUUCUAUGUCUUUUUUUAAUUGUACUUGUAUUAGAUUUUUAAGGCCUAUAAUCAUGAAAUAUCACUAGUUGCCAGAAUAAUAAAAUGAACUGUGUUUAAUUAUGAAUAAUAUGUAAGCUAGGACUUCUACUUUAGGUUCACAUACCUGCCUGCUAGUCGGGCAACAUGAAGUAGGACAGUUCUGUUGAUUUUUUAGGGCCAUACUAAAGGGAAUGAGCUGAAACAGACCUCCUGAUACCUUUGCUUAAUUAAACUAGAUGAUAAUUCUCAGGUACUGAUAAACACCUGUUGUUGUUCACUUUCCUCAUAAAAAUUGUCAGCUCUCUCUGACACUUAGACCUCAAACUUUAGCAUCUCUGUGGAGCUGCCAUCCACUGUAUAAUUUCGCCUGGCAACUGGACUGAGGGGAGUGUGCCCAGGCAGCUGCCAAGCACUCCCUCCCUGGCUUCAGGGUCAGAGUGCCCAGCGUUUAUCAGAGGCAGCAUCCAAGCCCAGAGCCAGUGUCGACUCUUCGGCUGGUGCCUUUCCUCUGAGGGGCUAUCAAUGUGUAGAUAAAGCCCUGAGUAGGCAAGAGCAGUGAGAUCCACUGCUAUGGUCUUGAUACAUCCUCAAACUUUCCCUUCCCAGCACAGAGGAAUAUUGGCUGGCAUGCAACCUGCAAAAGAAAAAUGCGAAGCGGCCGGGCACGGUGGCUCAUGCCUGUAAUCCCAGCACUUUGGGGGGCUGAGGUGGGCGAAUCAUGAGAUCAGGAGUUCGAGACCAGCCUGGCCAGCAUGGUGAAACCCCAUCUCUACUAAAAAUACAAAAAAUUAGCUGGGCGUGGUGACGGGCGCCUGUAAUCCCAGAUACUCAGGAGGCUGAGGUAGGAGAAUCACUUGAACCUGGGAGGUGGAAGUUGCAGUGAACCAAGAUCACGCCACUGCACUCCAGCCUGGGCGAUGGAGCGAGACUCCAACUCAAAAAAAAAAAAAGAAUAAAGAAAGAAAAGUGCGAUGCCCAGUCAAUCACAAAUAAGAUCAUCCUGGUUUAAAUCUACUCUCACAUGGAUCACAGUAUAAAUUUCUAUGUGCUGUGUUUUGUUCGUUUGUAUUUUGUAGAGAUGGGGUCUCGUUUUGUCGCCCAGGCUGGUUUUGAACUCCUGGCUUCAAGCGAUCCUCCUGUCUCGGCCUCACAAAGUGUUGAGACUACAGGCAUGAGCCACUGUGCCCAGCCUGUUCUAUGUUUUUAAGCUACACGAGAAUUUUUUUUUUAAUUAAUUCUCACUGUUUGUUCAGUCUGUCUUCAUCUAAGUUUGUGUUGCAGUUUAAAGUUAAAGUGACUUUUAAAGGCCACAUCACCUGAGACUAGGGUAAUCAUCUUUACUUCUGGUUCCUGAAAUCAUAUUUUUCCAGUGGACCAUCCUCCAGUGGCUGUGGUUGUUGAGCAUGCUUUCAGAACACCUAUGUGGCUUAAAACUUAGUUUAUGUUUUGUGUUCAACACUACGUGUAAUAUUUUAAAACUGUUUAAUGUGAUGUGAAUACAUUUAUGUACAUUUAUUUUUAAAUUUGUAAAUAGCUUUAAAUUGCUAUGGCAAUGUUUCUUUUAUAAAUCAUCAAAAUAAACCUUUGUGAAUUGA